GGUUUGGCCUUGGGUUCCGCUGUAGGGGAGGUCCCGUGCGAAAGAAUGAGGAGAUCCUGGGGCCUUACCUACUAGCGGAAUCGACUGAAGAGACGCCUGCCAGUGCGGGAGGUAGGAAGCUCGAUCCCCAAAGAAAAGAGCGAGUGGGCAGGCAGCUGCGAGACAGAACCGGAGUGUGCAGGGUCCCUAGAGGCCGGUUCCUGGUCUGUGCUGCUCUCCUGGAAGCCAUGGUACAGGCAGAGCUCAGGGCGAUCCCCAGGUGAGGGCAGCGGCUCUGCCUGGGAUUCCACCGCAGUACAACCGGGUAGAUGCGGGGUGGAGAAGAAAGGAUGUUGCCUGCACUGCUCGCCAAUAGCACCCUGAGAGGCUACAUUUGCAGAAGCAGCAGCAGCAGAAGACACAGCGCCGGUCCAGGAGGCGGCUCGAGCUGUUCGUAAAGUCGCCCGACAGCUUUUUCUCCGUAGUAUGCGAGUUGACAAAACAGCCAGAGAACAGGGCUCCCCAUUACAAUCUUUUCGAGAUCUUUUCCCUUGCUAACCGGAUCUGAUUUGUGCGAAAACAUGCCUUGCACUUGUACCUGGAGGAACUGGAGACAGUGGAUUCGACCUUUAGUAGCGGUCAUCUACCUGGUGUCAAUAGUGGUUGCGGUUCCCCUAUGCGUGUGGGAAUUACAGAAACUGGAGGUUGGAAUACACACCAAGGCUUGGUUUAUUGCUGGAAUCUUUUUGCUGUUGACUAUUCCUAUAUCACUGUGGGUGAUAUUGCAACACUUAGUGCAUUAUACACAACCUGAACUACAAAAACCAAUAAUAAGGAUUCUUUGGAUGGUACCUAUUUACAGUUUAGAUAGUUGGAUAGCUUUGAAAUAUCCCGGAAUUGCAAUAUAUGUGGAUACCUGCAGAGAAUGCUAUGAAGCUUAUGUAAUUUACAACUUUAUGGGAUUCCUUACCAAUUAUCUAACUAACCGGUAUCCAAAUCUGGUAUUAAUCCUUGAAGCCAAAGAUCAACAGAAACAUUUCCCUCCUUUAUGUUGCUGUCCACCAUGGGCUAUGGGAGAAGUAUUGCUGUUUAGGUGCAAACUAGGUGUAUUACAGUACACAGUUGUCAGACCUUUCACCACCAUCGUUGCUUUAAUCUGUGAGCUGCUUGGUAUAUAUGACGAAGGGAACUUUAGCUUUUCAAAUGCUUGGACUUAUUUGGUUAUAAUAAACAACAUGUCACAGUUGUUUGCCAUGUAUUGUCUCCUGCUCUUUUAUAAAGUACUAAAAGAAGAACUGAGCCCAAUCCAACCUGUUGGCAAAUUUCUUUGUGUAAAGCUGGUGGUUUUUGUUUCUUUUUGGCAAGCAGUAGUUAUUGCUUUGUUGGUAAAAGUUGGCGUUAUUUCUGAAAAGCAUACGUGGGAAUGGCAAACUGUAGAAGCUGUGGCCACCGGACUCCAGGAUUUUAUUAUCUGUAUUGAGAUGUUCCUCGCUGCCAUUGCUCAUCAUUACACAUUCUCAUAUAAACCAUAUGUCCAAGAAGCAGAAGAGGGCUCAUGCUUUGAUUCCUUUCUUGCCAUGUGGGAUGUCUCAGAUAUUAGAGAUGAUAUUUCUGAACAAGUAAGGCAUGUUGGACGGACAGUCAGGGGACAUCCCAGGAAAAAAUUGUUUCCCGAGGAUCAAGAUCAAAAUGAACAUACAAGUUUAUUAUCAUCAUCAUCACAAGAUGCAAUUUCCAUUGCUUCUUCUAUGCCACCUUCACCCAUGGGUCACUACCAAGGGUUUGGACACACUGUGACUCCCCAGACUACACCUACCACAGCUAAGAUAUCUGAUGAAAUCCUUAGUGAUACUAUAGGAGAGAAAAAAGAACCUUCAGAUAAAUCCGUGGAUUCCUGAACAGUAUGGAAAAGCAAACUGUGCAACUACUACAUUAUAUCAUUACCUGGUAUCCCAUGGAUUUUGUGCUUGGGACAGACCAUAAAUGAUGGAAAAUGUCAACACAAAAAUAGCUGAAAGCCAGGUACAACUACUGCAUUUAUAUAUGUAAGUUUUGUAUAUCAAAAAUAAUUGGUCUAAAUUUCCUAGACUUAGACUUGAUUUCUUAACAUUAGGGUAUCGCAUACUCAAAUGGUAGACAAUGACCCCAACUAAAUCUUCCUGAUGUUACACUGCUUUAUCAAGAGGAUGGACUUUUUUUUUUUUGAGACAGACAGAGUCUUGCUCUGUCACCCAGGCUGGAGUGCAGUGGCGCAAUCUCGGGUCACUGCAAGCUCUGCCUCCCAAGUUCAUGCCAUUCUCCUGCCUCAGCCUCCCAAGUAGCUGGGACUACAGGCACCUGCCACCAUGCCCAGCUAAUUUUUUUUUUUUCAGUAGAGACAGGGUCUCACCAUGUUAGCCAGGAUGGUCUUGAUCUGACCUCGUGAUCCGCCGACCUCGGCCUCCCAAAGUGCUGGAAUUACAGGCGUGAGCCACUGCGCCUGGCCAAGAAUGGACAUUUUUUAAAAAAACAUCAGUACUUCCUACCACUGCUGCAUGAGUAUAAUGCUCCGGAAUUAUCAGAAAGCAUAAUGCAGAAAUACGAAUUAGUGGAACUUAAUCAUGUGCCAUAUAAGCUUACCUAACAAACAGUUAUAUCCCUAUUCCUCAACUGAAUGUCUUUCAAUAAAUAAGAAUUUAUCAUUUAUUUUCUGCAACUUUUUUAUGUCUCAUUCUUUAAACAUUAAAAACCCUUAAUAUUUUAACAAAAAUUUCUUGAUUAGAGGCACAGUGAAAAAGAAGUCAAAAAAAAAAGUUCUACUUUUCAUCAGUGCUAUUAAAGGUGGCAGCAAAUGUAAAUCUUGGCUGAAUGGUCUUAAUUACUCAUUAAACCACAGUCAGAAAGACAUAUAGGUGCUAUUUGGGAAAACUUUUUAUUACCUAGGAUGGGGUUUCUCUAAUUGCUAAUCACAACCCCACUGGGUCAUGUUUGACAUUUUAUAAUGAAAAUAAAACAGAAAGUGCCAUAGUAUGUUACAGAAAGCAAAGAUGAGUAUUGUUUCUCAAAGCCUUUGCUUUAUGUAUUUAUACACAUACUCAUUCAUAUCUAUCUAUAUAUAUAGAGAGAGAUAGUGGUUCACAGUAAUCAUACAAAGUCUUUAUUCCAUCCACUAUUAUAAACAUUUCUAUUAAAACUAAAACUGGGCUCUAUGUAAAAACCCCAAAGAUACACACACAAAAAAAAUCUGUUUGUUAGAACUCAAGUGAAUUCAGUAAAGUUGCAGAAUACAAAAUCAACAUACAAAAAGCAUUAGCAUUUUUAUACAUAAAUAAUGAAAAUAAUGACCUAACUGAAAAAUUAAGAUGCCAUUUAUGAUAGCAUAAAAAAAAUACUUACUUAGGAAUAAAUUUAACACCAAGGCAGUAAAAGAUCUGUAUGUACACUGAAAACUAUGAAACACUGAUGAAAGAAAGACACAAAUAAAUGGAAAGGUAUCCCGUGCUCAUGGAUCAGAAUAAUACUGUUAAAAUGGUCACACUACCCAAAGCAAUUCAGAAUCAAUGCAAUCCUAUCAAAAUUCCAAUGGCAUUAUUUACACAAACAGAAAAAAAUCCUAAAAUUCAUAUGUAACGAUAAAAGACCCUGAAUAGGCAAAAGAAUACUGAGGAAAAAAUGUUGGAGACAUCACAUUUCCUAAUUAUAAAUUAUACUACAAAACUAUAGUAAUCAAGACAGUAUGGUACUGGUAUAAAAACACAUACACAGGCCAGUGGGACAGAAGAAAGAGUCCAGAUAUAAAUCCAAACAUACACAGUCAACUAAUUUUUGACAAAGACACCAAGAAGACACAUCGGGGAAAGAACAGUCUUCAUUAAGUGUUCUUAAUGAAGAUGCUGGGAAAACUGCACUUCCACAUGCAAAACAAUGAAAUCAGACCCUUAUCUUAGACCUACACAACAAUCAAUUCAAAAUGGAUAAAAGACCUAAAUGUAAGACCAGAAACUAUAGAAGAGAACAUAGGAGAAAAGUUCCUGGACACUGACCCUUGGCAAUGAUUUUUUGGAUAUCACACCAAAAGCUCAGUCAACAAAAACAAAAACAAAUGUGACUACAUCAAACCAAAAAGCUUCUGACAGUAAAAGAAACAGUCAACAAAAUGAAACAGUAGCCUACAGAUUGAGUAAAAAAUAUUUGUAAGGCAUAUAU